CUGGCGGCGGUGUCCGACCGCGAACGCGGAGGGCGGCCGGGCAGGUGGGGGUGCCGCCCGAAGGGCCGGGCCGGGUGCUGGGGCUGCAGGCGCCGCCGCCGCGCUGUCAGCGUCCGCCCCGUGGCUCUCGGCCGGAGGAGCGGCGGCCGCCGGCCCGGGGCGCGAGUCUGGCUGAAAGGAGCGGGCGCGCCGGGACCACCCGGCGAUGCUGUCGCCGCCGCCGCCGCCUCUGUAGCGAGCACCCGAGCCCGCCGCGGAGAAAGGCUGAAGAAAGCUCAGUCUCAAUUGUGUUUCCUGCCUGUCAGCCUCUUGCCUCCUAAACGUGUACCAUUUCCACUUGAUGUCAUCACGCAGAAGGGGUGAAAGAGACUCGGUGACAGAUACAGAUAUAUGCUGUAAGUCUACAGCAACACCCGAAGGCCAACCUCUACAGUGGGUAACUUGUUCUGAAUGCCUGUGCUGGCUACGAGGAAAAUGACUGGAGAGAGGAGCCAGGAAAAGCCCAGCUGCACACAUUACCAUGAAUCUCCUCAGACAGCUUUCUAAGUGAGGAGCUGGGGUAUCUGAAUUGCCCCUAGGAGGCUCGUUAAGUUCUAAGAAGUUUGGAGGAGAAAUAAUCAUAUUGGAAUGUUUUCCUUUGGAACCACUGUUUCCAGAAGCCACGGUUUUUGAAAAUUGCCAUUGCUGCUGGCCUCGUCAUAUUCCUGGGUGUUUUGAGAGCACAUGUGCCCCCUGGCUGGCUCUGAGCUGCCUGUCACUGAGAGCACCCUGGCCUUUGACAAAAAUGGGCAAAUAAGAUACCCUCCCAUAGGGCUGUUGUAAGGAUGAGAUAAGGCACGGAGAAAACUGGGCACAGUUCCUGAGUGUCUCACUGUAGCCUCACCCCUGAAGCUGGGGCAGCUCAGGCGCUUGGGUAAGUGUUUUCUCCUCUUUUCCGUCCUCCCUCCCCUCUUCAAUAAGCACUUAUUGGACACCUACUACUGGUAGGAAUAUGGUAUAGAUGCAGUGUUUAUGCAGAGUGGACACCCUUGUGAAGGACUUCAGUGAUUUAAAGUUUGAUUUUAAAAAUGAAAAUAAAAAAUAAAGUUUGAUUUAAAAUAUUGACACAAAGUAGUGAUGGGAGGGAGGGAUGGGGUGAGUACAGCCUGUCUGUUUCUGAUGGGUCAGAAAGGUAAGACCUGAAAUGGUUUAUUUGCACCAACCACAGUCAGAUCAUAAGUUUUUUUUUUUUUUUUUUAAUCAUUGUGGAUAUCAGCAGAUGGUCUUGAGGACCAAACAGAGAAAGGUCACUGGCUGAUGCACCUGGUGGUAUGUACCCUGGGGAGUGGCCAUGAUUCUCUAAUUUGAUUGGCUACACAGCCAAUCAUGUAUGAAAGCAAACAUGAUGACUGGGCAUUUCCGUGUGCCCAGAGCUGCACUAGCCAUUCAGGGGUGCAUGCUGUCUGCCUGGAUGGAGCUUCCUGAGUACGUGUGUACCUCACAGCCUAAGGGUGAAGUGCUCAGGGGGAGGCUGCAAGGUAGGAGGUGAGUAAGCUCUCAUCAGUUCCCUGAGCUCAAACAAGCGGUUUGGAUAAACCAUAAAAUUGUCUAUAUUUUAACCUCUCUGUUUUUAGGGUAGCAUUCACAUACAGGUUUACUUUGUUGUCCUGAAUUUAUAUUUUUUUCAUAGCAAAUGAUCCAAACUGAAAGCCUCCUUUUUCCAAGAUUCCCUUAGUAAAUAUUUAUUGUGCUCUAAUCAAGUAUAUGGAGCUUGAGUCUGCCUCUCAGUAACUUGAAAUUUAUCAGUGAUUAGAACUGUUAACCAAGUUUGAUGGUGAUCAUAAUAGUGAUGUGUUAUUUUUAACUCUGCUUUUCAAGAGUAGAAAAGAAUUAUUUUAAGGGUAUAGAAUAAUUCUAGCAAGUGCUCAAAGAAAUUUUGUUUUGUCACCUAUUUCACUUAAAAACCACAUAUGAAAAAUGAGAGGACUGUAAUAGUGAUAAUGAUAGCAUUCUGCAUUCAAGGAGUUAUUCUGUGCCAGAUGAUAUGUCAAGGGCUUUGCACACAUUUCUCAUUUUAUCAGCCAGAAACUGUAUGAGGUCGUGCUUUCUUAGUGUUCACACUUUACUGACAAGGGGCAUUGAAGAAUAACAAGGUUAGAUAACUUGCCCACGUUCAAGCAGCUUGUCAGUGGAAGGUCUUCCAUUUGAUUCCAGACUCGUGUCUUUUCAACACUACCGUAUUAUUGCCUUAGGUAGAAUCCACAGUUAGGUGGAUUGAGAAAGAAGAAGCUCUAAAAGAGACAGGAAGAAAAUAUUGGCUAAUUCACCCCAAUAUGUCCCUGCCAGGUUUGGAUGAAGAGGAACCAUAUUUAGACAUCUUAGAGAUAGGCAGUAAGCACUGAGAAUGAGAAUUGCCUCAGGUCACACAGUACUUGAUAGAACUUACCCAGAAGCCAGGUGCUCCUCAAACUCAUUUGAUGAUGUCAGGGCAUGGUGGCUCAAACCUGUAGUCCCAGCAAUUUGGGAGGCUGAGGCGGGAGGAUGGUUUGAGGCCAGGAGUUCAAGACCAGCCUGGGCAACAUAGUGAGACCACUUCUCUUAAAGAAAACCCAAGCCAAACCAAAACAACAGCAACAACACUCAUUCAAUGAGGAUUCAGUCCAUACAAUUACAUGCUUUCAAACUAAUUGGUAGAGGAGAGAUCCAUUUUGUUUUGGAUAAUCUAAAACCAUAGUUUUAAGAACUUUCCAUUUGGGUUAAAUUUUGAAAUUUCUUUCUGCAUAUUUUGGAACAGUGCACAGGGUUUGGCAUUAGCUCAGUGGCCACUUUGGGCAGGUUACUUCAAUCCCCUUCGUGUGGCUGUUGGGGGAAAGAGGUGCUAAUGACACCUAAAGCUUUGUAGUUAUUCGUUGUAAUUGCUCAGGGAUUGGCCACCUGUGACACUUUUGACAUAAUUUUAGAAAAGGGAGCCAAGUUCUCAAAAGUAAUUAUGGGUCCAGGGAAAUUCCUCAGGGUUAACUUCAAGGUAGCAAAAAUGUAGAUUUUCUAAAAAGGAAAAUUUCUGGCCAUGUCACAUAGUGAUUGGGUCUUGGUUUUUAUGUGUUAUGUACUGGAGACCAUUUGCCCCAGACAAAGGAUUUAGUACUCAGGUUGUGAGCUGGUGAAGCCCCCGCAGGGCAGUACUCCCCUGUUUCUCCACCCAUCUCCCCUCAGUGGAGCGAGAGAGAGGAGGCAGGGAGUCAUAGUACGGGUUGACACAGACUUGGCUCCCAAACCCCGGGGGAUUCACAGCUGACAAUGACGGGAAAGUAGGAAUGCUCGAAGGCCCUCUCCAGGCUCCCCUUCCCUGUUCUCCCCUGGGCUGGUGCAGAGUCCAGGAUCUCCACGGGCUAUUGGUUUGUGCUGGAGAUUCUGCAUCCCUGUGGAUCAUUCUCCAGUCUUUUGAGACCUCUGUGGGCUGUGUCCUGGCUCUCUUGCCCUCUGGCUUCAUGUUGGGUUAGGCCACUGGCAGGAGACUGAGGGACAAGAUGGAGAAUUCUGAGUACUUUCCUCCUCCCUGCCUUAGCCCCUUGUCCCCAUCUGUACAUCAGCUCCUGCCGGGCAGGCCUCUUCCGUGGCUCCAAACUUUCACUGCUUCUGGUGACAGCUGCUGUCUUGCCCCCUCCACCCUGAGGUCAGUAGGGGCUUUCCACAGGUGCUGGUCUCUGGGGGCCUUGUAGGACCCUUAACCCUGCAUAGACCUACGUACAGUUCCUUCCGAAGCCUCUCUGCAAAUACUACUAAGAAGGUAACUGUGUUAGGCUGAGGCCACGUACAGCCUGGGGGGCUGUGUGUAGUAAGUUUACGGAUGUUGCUUGCUAUUCUGUUACUGACUUCUGGUUUUAUCUGGGGGAAGGUGAUGGUAGCAGGGUGGUAUUGAUUUUUUUUUCUUUGAUUAUAUUUGACAUAUAAACCUAGAGCUUCUCUUUGAGGCUAUGGAAUCAUUCAAAAAAUGUGGCAUAAUUACUAAUGGUUAGAAAAAUUGUGGAAGCACUGAUAUCUUGCAAAAAUAUUGAGAAAGCUAGAAAACUUUAGCUGUUGUGGUGGGUCAGAGAGAGAGGGAGAGGGAGAGACAGGGCAGAGUUAGUAAGAGCCCGCUCUUCCUGCUACCUCAUAGGGUUUUAGUUAGCUGAUGUGAGAGGAGCCCAGAGGCGCUUUUGAAAUCAGGUGUCUACUGUGUGCCAGGCACAGUUCUAGAUGCUGGGAAUGCAGCCCCAAAUGAAACACACAGUGGGGCUUAUGUUCUGGGGAGAUAGCAGGUGAUUCCAAGUAAAAUCAGAUGGGUAGAUUACAUAAGGUGUUAGAAGAUGAUCUGCAUCUGGAGAAAAAUAAUCACACGAAGGGAAGCGUGAGUGUGGUGAGAGCUUGCAAUGUGUAAAAAGGCAGUCAAGGAAGACCUUCUGAAGAAAGUGAUAUUUGAGCUCAGACUUGAAGGAGGUGAAAAGGAAAAAUACAUCAGCAUUUGAGAGCAGAGAUUCCAAGCAGAGGGAAGAGUAGGUGUGAAGGCCAGGCCAUUGACUGAAGGGGAAGACUGUGGGUAGAGCAGGUUUGGGAAGUGGGUGGGAGGGAGACCGGGAAUUCCAUUUUGGAAAUCUUAGCUUUGAGACGCCUAUGAGAAACCCGAGGAAUGAUCUCAAACGCAUGACUGUUGUCAGUGUUUAGUAGUUUUCAGUUUCAAAUCGUAUCACCAUUGGUGUCUUGCUUUCUCUGAGGUGUGUUUUAAGAAAAAUAAAUGUUUACACCAUGGUUUUGGUAGUGAUUUUGAGAGUAAGCCUAGGGGCAGAAUAUGCAAUGCCUAUAUUUUCCCUUGAUUCAAAAACCACCUUUGCAUAGUUAACAGAUUCAAGGACACUUGCGGGAAUUUUUUCUGAGUUGAGAGAGUUUUGCCACUGUUUGACCAGCUCUGACUGUAACAAUACCAAACCUCUUUUUAGAGCAGAGCUGUGUUUUAUGGCAUUAUGCAAUGAAAGUUUCAAGUCGCCCACAAAAGCAGACCCCAUGCAAAUAGAAAUAGCACAUUUCUCAAAGCCCCAAUUUGCUUGUAUGUUAAAGCUUGCUGCCCUGUUAGAUGUAUUUUUGCUUUUAAAUGUUACUCUGAUACCUCUUUUUUUGUGUUGUUCUCUCCACUUCUUGCUUUUUAUUUAUUUCUGAAAGUUCUGUUUUCUUGGUGGCAAUGUCACAGUUGCUCUGAAUGGUGAGGUGAGACUAAGUAUGGGGGAGGAGUACCGGUGUUUGCUGAGCAGCUACUAUGUGCACUACUGGGCUGGAUACCUUGCUACUUACCCCCAUUUAAUCCUCAUAACAAUAUUUUGAUGGAGGUGUGAUUGUCCCUGAGUUACACAUGAAGAAGCAGAUACUCAGUAAGGUUAACUUGCAUAAGGCUACAUUAUUAAUUGGUGACAAGAGUUGGGACUCAAAUCCAGACUAGUGGAUUUCCAAGCUCUGGAGUCUCCAUAGCUCAAGCAAAGCUUUCUCUGCAGGCAGUUUAGUGCUUCUAGAUAUCAGUGCAUUGCAUUGUCUGGCUUUGUUACUAAUGAAGGUGAGGAGAGCAGUAUUAAUAAUUCUAUGUCUGGUGCUUCUUUCCUAAAUGUUUCUAUGAAUUUCCCAGAAUGUACAGAAUACCUUUCUGGUGCCAGGUGUUUGCCCAGUGUUGAGUUGGUGGCAGCAAGUACUCGUGGAGCUUACACCCUAGCAAAUAUUUAGUAAGGAAUCACUCAGGAGAAGAGUGUUGCGGGGAAAGGAAGGAGUAAGUGCUCAACGAAUGUGCAUCUGUGAGUUGGGGACCACUUUUCCCCUUACCUCAACCUGUAAGACAAUGAAUUGUCCAGGUCAGGGAGGUAGAGAAGAAACUCUUGGCAGCAGAAGCAACAUGAACAGAGGCUCAAUGUAGCGAUGAGAUUGAAUGAGAUGAGAUUGCAUAGGCACAGUGGGUAGAGGGAGAUGAGAAGGGGGCCUAUUAUUUGGUAAUAAGAGACUGUUGUACCUUUGAGUUUUUAUUACAUGACACCAUGGAAGCUCCCCAAAGACAGUUUUUUGGGAUUGUUUUUUAUUAAAAAAGAAAGAAAAGAUUGAGGAAAAGGCAAGAACAAGAGAGAGUGUUUGGGUUGAGAAUUAUGAAGUGUGUAUCUUUGUCCUUUCAGGUGCUAUAAUAUAAUACCAUAGACUGGGUGGCUUAUAACAACAGAAAUUUAUUACUCACAGUUCUGGAGGCUGGGAAGUCCAAGAUCAAGGCAGAUUUGGUGUCUUGUGAGAGCCCAUUUUCUGGUUCAUAAAGGGCAUCUGCUGUGUCCUCACAUGGUGGAACGAGAUAAGUGAGCUCCCUUGGACUUAUUUUAUAAGGGGCACUAACCCCACUCAGGAGGGCUGAGUCCUCAUCACCACGCCCCCCCACACAAAGCCCCACCUGUUAAUACCUUCACAUUGGUGAUUAGGUUUCAACAUAUGCAUUUUGGGGAGACACAAACAUUGAGACUGUAGCAGUGUGCAUUGACUACAUUUUUGAACAGACUUAUGGUCAGGUUCAUCAAACAAAAGUGAUUCCUGAGAGGAGGGUUUCAAUGAGGAGUACUAUUAUUCGGGCUGCCUCUGCUACGGGAGGUCAGUUCCUUGAAGAAUGAAGAUUGCAAGUGCAUUAUAGGGCAGUAAUCUAUAGCCUUGUUUUGGAGGAAAAUUGACUUCACAUAAACCCUUCGAUGUCUUAAAGUACAAAUGUAUCUACCAUUUUAAAAUGAAACGUUAUAAAAACUUUCCAAACCUGCUUUAAGGGAAGCAACUGUUUUGACUAUAAAUUUCAAACUUCUGCACCUAACUAGGAGAGAGAUUGAUGUUCUCCCAGCACAAAAGCUCCCAGGUGGCUGAGUCAGUUUGAGCAGCGGCGGCCUGAGUGGUUUGCUCUGCGUGCCCAGCUGGCUGGGGCUGAUGUGUGGGCUUGGCGAGAGUUCUGGCACUCUGAGCGGACUUCAUUGUUUAAUGAGGUUUUAUUUGAGAUCCCUAGCAUUGCUCUUCUUACACAGCACAGCCAAAACUGUCACCUCCACAAGUGAAUAAGAAAAUCAUCUUGGGUGGGUGCAGUGGCUUACGCCUAUUAUCCCAUUGCUUUGGGAGGCUGAUGGGGGAGGAUAGCUUGAGUCCAGGAGUUUAAGGCUGCAAUGAGCUAUGAUCAGGCCACUGCACUCCAGCCUGGGCAACAGAGUGAGAUCCUGUCUGUGAAAACAAACAAAAAACCCACCACCCACCAACAAAAUAAAAUCAUCUCAACUCAGCCUCUGCACUUGUAUAACAAUCCUACAGUGGCACCAAUGUUUUCAGCACUCGUGUCCACUUAUGGCCCUCAGGAGGAAUGGAAGGAAUAAAAUGAAUGAAAUAGGCUCUUUGUUAGUUGCCCUCUAUAAAUCGUAAAUCACUGGGGCGAGUAGGUGAAUAAAUGCUUUUUUUUUUUUGUUUUAAAAGGCCAUUGCGAAUAUCUAAAGGUCAUCAGAGCCUUUUAAAACUAGGUUAAAAUGCAUUUUGCACCUUCCCUUGAUAAAUCAAGUUUCAUUGCAUCUUACUGCCCUCAUUAGAGGUACAGGUUUUAAGCACAUAUGACCUACCGACCCGUGCUAUGGUUACACUUAUUCUCUCCUAAACCCCAGUCAUUGGGUAGACACAAGAUGAAUAAUUUGUUGGCCUGUUUGUGCUAGUGAUUUCAAAAAGGAAGCUUAGCUUUUAGAUAAAAAAAAUGCUACUGUAAAUAUUCUGCAGUCCUGAACAUGUUUCUUACACACAAACAAUAAUACCAACAAGCACAUAAAACCCACCAGAGCCAGUGUGGCUUUUUCCACCAGAUCGACAUAAUGGAUGGUUUUCUUUUGCCAAGGUGAAGCAUAGUGGUAAGGUAUUGUUUUUAUGAUUUUCCAAUAGUCUGUUACUCAUAACUCCUCUCAGGUUUGUUGUGUGAGAUUUUAUAAAAGAUAUUUGCUCAUGAAUUUGACUUUGGCUUUCAUACAAAAUGAUUAGUAUCAUUUGUGCUCUGUAGAGUUUUAAACUUUGAGCUUUUUAGAUUCCUAGAUACUAUGGGGCCUGCCCUCCCCUCCCCUCCCGUCUCCCUCCUUCCCUCCCUCCUUCCCUCCCUCCUUCCCUUCCUUCCUUCCUCUCUUCCUCCCUUCCUCCCUUCCUUCCUUUUCUCUUAAUUUCUUUCUUUCUUUCUUUCUUUCUUUCUUUCUUUCUUUCUUUCUUUCUUUCUUUCUUUCUUUCCUUUCUUUCUGUCUUUCUCUCUUUCUUUUUUCUUUUUCUUUCUCUCUCUCUUUCUUUUCUCUCAUUCUCCUUAUCUGCUUAUUAUUUAUUUAUUUUUACUGUGGUAAAAUACACAUAACAUAAAAUUGAGCAUUUCUAUCAUUUUUAAGUAUACAGUUCAGUGGUGGUAAAUACAUUCACAAUGUUGUACAACCAUAACUUCCAUCCAUCUUCGUAACUCUUUUCAUCUUGUAAAACUUAAACUCUAUGUCCAUUAAAUAAUAAGUCCUCUUUCCCCAUUCCCUGGCAACCAUGAUUCUAUUAAUUCUUUCUGUCUUUAUAAUUUUGACUACUGUAAGUACCUCAUGUAAGUGGAAUCACAUAGUAUUUGUCUUUUUGUGACUGGCUUAUUUCACUGAACAUAAUGUCCUCAAAAUUCACCCAUGUCGUAACGUGUCAGAAUUUCCUGCUGUUUUAAGGCUGAAUAAUAUUCCAUUGUAUGGCCAUACCAUAUUUUGCUUUGCCAUUCAUCUGUCUGUGGGCAUUUGGGUAUUUUCCCAUGUUUUAGCUAUUGUAAAUAAUGUUGCUAUGAACAUGGAUGUAGAAAUAUCUCAUCAAGACCCUGCUUUCAAUUUUUUAGGGUAAAUACUCAGAGGUGGAAUUGCUGGAUGAUAGGGUGAUUUUAUUUUUAAUUUUUUGAGGAACUGACAUACUGUUUUAAAACAACAGUUAUUGCUAUAGAUUUUUAAACAAUAGCCAACAAUCCUGAAGGAUGUUAAUAUCUAAUUUAGUGAGGCCUAAGUUGAGAAACCAGUGAAACUGGCUAGAAACACACCAUUGACCAUAGUCAUUUCUACUGAGAGAUGGCUUUUCUGUAGGGUGUGCACGAGUUGAAAAGAAAAUAGUUUUCUCAGUCAUUCAGCAACAGUUGUUCAGGUGCUCUUGGCACUUACCUGGCAUUCUAAAAUCCUUCCCACAGAGCAGGUUGUCAAAUACCCGGCUAGCUCUGAACUUUAAAAUGCAAGACAUUUAGAAGGAAAACACAUUUAAACCACUUCCAUUCUGUAGAGUCAGGUUGCUGUGAAUGGAGAGGUUACCAGAACCAGUCAUGAAACAGGGUGAUAUGGUUUGGCUCUGUGUCCCCACCCAAAUCUCAUCUUGUAGCUCCCAUAAUUUCCACAUGUUGUCAGAGGGACCUGAUAGGAGAUGAUUGAAUUAUGAGGGCGGGUCUUUCCCGUGCUGUUCUUGUGAUAGUGAAUGGGUUUCCUGAGAUCUGAUGGUUUUAAAAAUGGGAGUUUCUCUGCACCAGCUCUCCCUUUGCCUACUGCUGUCCACAUAAGAUGUGACUUGCUCCUCCUUGCCUUCCACCAUGAUUGUGAGGCCUCCCCAGCCAUGUGGAACUGUGAGUCCAUUAAACCUCUUUCUUUUGUAAAUUGCCCAGUCUCAGGUGUGUCUUUAUCAGCAGCGCAAAAAUAGACUAAUACACAGGAAGAGACAGAAACUCACUCAUGAAGGUGCUCAAUAGUCAAGCAUUUGACUUUUUGCCAUGAAGGAAGAGAGAGGCCAGAGAAGAGUCUCUUGCAGGUCCUAACUUUUGUGAAAACAAGUCUCCAGGGAAACAAAGCCCCUGUGACAACUCGCUUGGGUGUGACAGCUGCCAGCCUUGUUCCAGCAAUGACAGCAGCCUCCAGAAGAGAAAUGGGCCACUGGGGAAUGUGAAAGAAUGUGUUUUGCUUUUAUGUCUGGUGUGUGGUCAGCUGUCAAUUAAUAGAACUGUGCUGUGAGUUAGAAAACUAGGCCACAAAGGGGCUUUCAGGAAAUGUUUAUAAUGUGGAAUUAAUCUGACACUCACUGUGUUGGCUAGAAAAUGGAACAAUGGCUUGUUCACGACAAAUUGUUCAGUAGGAAAAAAUGUCAUAAGCAGAAUUGCUGGUUAAGAAAAUAACAAAGUGAAUAUGAUCAACUUGUGGUAAAAAUACAUGUGAACCCUUAAUAAAACUCAGAGCUGAAUUUAGUUUUGUGAUUUGCUAUUAGAUUCCUUGUGCUGGCUUUAAAGUGAUACCUUUUAGUAUAGCCCUGGGGUCAAAUGCAACCCACCUCAUGUUUUUGUAAAUAAAGUUUUAUUGGAACACAGUCAUGUCCAUUUGUUACGUAUUGUCAAUGGCUGCUUUCUGUUACAGUGGUAGAGUUGAGCAGUUGUAACAGAUGCUGUGUGGCACACAAAGCCUAAAAUAUUACCAUCUGUCCCUGUGCAAAGAAUGUAUUGACCCAUGUUCUACAGCCUUGCCACUGAAAGCAGGAUUAGUGAUUUACUGCCGUGUUGGAGAUUGAGAAGCACUAGUCUAAGACCAGUUCUUCACUUGCGGUUUCAUGGAGAGGCUUAAGUGAUUGCACUCCAUGAAAUUAUACGCACAAUUCUGUUUUUGUACAAAUGUGUAUUUUUCUGCAUCUCUACCCACUCAGAGGUAGAGGGGUUUGUGAGCCUUAUCACUUUCUCAGAAUGACUUGUAACCCCCCAAAGUUAAGAAUCCCUAGACUAGAAAGAGUGGCCUUGACUCAGUAUGGGUUCAUGUCUGAAAUGAUGGUUGGAAAGAUCUUACUCCUCUACACCAAAAAUAGAUCCAGCUCAAGUUCAUUUAUUCAUUAUUCUUAAAUAAAGAGUAUAAAUUUGCAGCACAGCACAGAGGUGGGCUAUGUCAUUUUGUAACUAUUAUUAAUGGAGAAGGGACUAUUUCAUGAAUAUUGGUUCCUUGUGCCUUAAUAACUAGUGUCAUGUUAUGUUGCGGGUCUGGAGAUAUUUAUUACAUGCCUCUCCCACCUUGAUAAAGUGAAAGCUUUCUAAUGUCCAGAAUUUUAGGCCUUUGUAGUGACUUUUAAUGGGAAACUGGAAAUCACUGCUAGUUAGCUUGACAGUGUUAUUAAACUUCUAUCAUGUAUGGAACCCUGCAGGAAUUUCUAAAAAGCAGAAGAUGAAAUCUGAAAUGGACCGAGCCUGACUUCUGAUCAGCUUCCCCAUGAACUGCUGCUCCAUGUGCCCCAUGGGUCUUUCUCACCCCAUGCCAGCCUCCUGCAGUAGGUGAGUGGGAUCUGAUGAACAUUAUGUUUACUGAAGUUGUAGAAGAUGACGGCCAAGUUCAGCUUGGAUUGGAGAAGUGUAAGGAAGAAAUGAACACACCUGUGAGUACUGGAUGCCUGUGAGCUUGCCAUUACCUGCACUGCAAAGACACAGGGCGGUGGCCUCUGAGAAGCAGCUCCUUCCCCUUCACCUUGGCCUUGCCCUUCCUGCUCACGGUCCACCAUGGAGACGCUGUCCCAGGACUCUCUGCUGGAAUGUCAGAUCUGUUUCAAUUACUACAGCCCCCGGCGCAGGCCCAAGUUGCUGGACUGCAAGCACACCUGCUGUUCAGUGUGCCUGCAGCAGAUGAGGACCAGCCAGAAGGAUGUGCGGUGCCCCUGGUGCCGCGGUGUCACCAAGCUGCCUCCCGGCUUCUCCGUGUCGCAGCUCCCGGACGACCCGGAGGUCCUGGCUGUCAUCGCCAUUCCACACACUUCCGAACACACCCCGGUCUUCAUCAAACUUCCCAGCAAUGGGUGCUACAUGCUGCCCCUGCCCAUCUCCAAGGAGCGUGCGCUGCUGCCCGGAGACAUGGGCUGCCGCCUGCUGCCCGGGAGCCAGCAGAAGUCCGUCACCGUGGUGACCAUCCCUGCUGAACAGCAGCCUCUGCAAGGUGGGGCUCCCCAGGAGGCGGUGGAGGAGGAGCAGGACAGGCGGGGCGUGGUGAAAAGCUCCACCUGGUCGGGGGUGUGCACUGUCAUCUUGGUGGCUUGCGUCUUGGUCUUCCUCCUCGGCAUCGUGCUUCACAACAUGUCUUGCAUUUCUAAGCGCUUCACUGUGAUAUCCUGUGGCUGAAGAGGGCUGCAGGGAAGUCUCUUGUGGGUGCCAACUUAGGGGUUGAGCAGGUUGAUGAUGAGAUCCCAGUGAGAAGAUGGGGGGCAACACUGACCAUUUGGUGCUGAGCGCUGGCCUCUGGGUUGCCUCUUGAUUACCCCAAGACAGACACAAAGGGCAGAAGGUGCGGUCUCAACAAGAUACCAGGUGAAUUGUUCUGAGUGUUGAUGGCAACAGCUUGGAAGAUGAUUGCAUGCAUCCUCAUAAUCAUGUAUUCAAUGGACUGUAAUUUAUGAUUUUUCAAAAUCAUGUUACAAGAUAGACAUAUUCUACUUAGACGUUAAACUGUACAAGUGCGUACAAUGUGACCUUCUCUAAAUGCGGUAGAUUCAAACAAAGAUGCUCUGUAGACAAGUAGAAUUAAACCUGCGAAUCCGUGUAAAAAUUCAGUGAAGACAUGCACUGCUGGCUUCUUUAUUUUUUUUUUCUUUUUAUUGAAACCCAGUCUUCAUUUAGUUGCUAAGGCUUUUAAUACAUUUUGAAUGGCACCAAAACAAAAUAAGUCAAAAUGGACAGUCAUUUUAUUUGGAGGAAAUAUUUGAACAAGUGUCUCCAAUGUGUUGUGUUUUGUCAUGAACCUUCAUUUUCUUCACUUGUAAUUAGAGCUUGCUACGUGUUUAUGGAACUGAAAGCUCAACAGGGGAGCAAUAAACCGAGAAAUCAUGAGAAAUGUCUAAUCCCAUGGGAAAACCUGUAUGCCGAUUUUCCUCAAGCCAUCUCACAAAAUAAGAAUUUCAAAUGUAAAUAUUGUGUAUUUGUGUGUGUAUGUGUGUGUGUCUAAUUUGAUUUACCUCAGGUGUUUGAGUCUUUGCUGAAGAAUCCUGGGAUGAAGACUUCAUUGGGCAUGAAUGAGUCAAGUCUCUGAAGCGGUGGCCACUUCUUGGACAUCUUGACCCAGCGAGUGGUCUCCUACACGUCACCUGCAACACUCGCUCCUCUUCUGUGUAUUUAAGUCCUGCAUUUUGUAAGAGGCAAAUGGAGAGUAACAGAAGAGUGUCUUUUCUCCUGGUUUUGGAGUCUUGCACUGGCCAUGAGUGUUGUGACUGAUGGUCAACCCAGGCGGGCAUUUUAAUAAAUGGCCUGUGAUUCUUUUUUGAAAGAUGCUCUUCCACAAGAGUUAAGCCAGUUAGAAUUCCUGUUUCCUCUUGUUGAUAUGAGAGAAGAUCUCCUGUAUUUUAACACGUUUUUACCAAGAAAGGUGGCAAGGUAAACUAACAGCUCAAAUUCCCAAUAUAAGUGGACCAGUUCCUCAUAAACUGUCAAAUGUUCUUAAAUGUGUAAUGAUCUAUAGAUGCUCAUGAAGAAAGAUCUGCUACAAGUACGUGAUAAAUUCCUAUCCCUGGGUGCAUGUGCAUUCAGAAAUAGCUGUGAGCUUUACAGCUCUCAUCUAACUUCUUUUAUGGAAUUCAUGAAGCAAGUGGUAUGUGACAAGGACUCCACUUAUAAAUAUAACUGUUUUUAUGUUCCACUGAAUCCCUGAAAAUGGUGAGGAGGGUGGGGGGAAGUGAAGGAAAGACAAGCAGGGCUAAUUCCAAAAAGCAAGGCUAGAAAAUAGCCCUGUGAGGUCAAGACAAUUUAAUUUAUUUACAUGCUGUCUGUUAUCUUCAAGCAGCACAAAAUAUGCAUAUAAAAGUGAUGGAAUUAAUGUGAAAUAAAACAAAAAUAUAAUGGCUAGAAUACAAAGCUAAUACUGCUAAUUGGCAUGAGAAUUCAACAUAAAAUUGUGAGCUCUGAUUUUUCAAAUUGAUCAUAAAACCUUUAGGAAAUGUAUUUGAAAGCUCAAAAUAGAAAUUAGGUUAAAAUGCCAUUUUAUUGUGUAAGCUCUUGGGCAUUAUACAACAAAUAAUCUAGGAUUUAUUUGGUAUUAAUAAUUUAGGUGUCAUAUUAGCUGAAUACUAUCCUCUAUUACAUAACAUAAUAUACUGUUGGGUUAGUGUCAAUUUCUCAAACUCUCCCAGGCUGCCAUAAUGCAUGUCUGACCUAAUUUCUAUUUCUCUUGGAGGAAAAUACACACACACACACACCACAGAAGUGUUGCAUUAAGAAUGCUACAUUUCGAAUAGACUUUGCCCUUGCAAUUUUAAGCUAUGCCAUAUUCAGAUUAAUUUUGUGAGUGAUAUCUGCAUAUGUUUCUGUACAGUGUGAAAUGACUGACCCUGUAGUAUAGUACGUGAUAGAGUUCUACUUGUUAAAGUAGGUUAGAUAUAGACACUAAUGUGUGUGAUGAUAGUGUCCUGUGUUUCUUAGUGCAAAUCUGUAGAGUAAAAAUGUCCAUAGAACUUUUACUUAAAAACAAUCCCAUGCUAGAGUUGCCAUUAAGCAGUGCAAAAUUAAUCGGCUGUAUGGUAGAUUCUUGACCUUAAAUUUAACAACAACAACCAAAAUCAGAUUUUUUUUGUGAGUCUUACUGACCUAAGAAACAUUGUUUAAAUUGUUUAAAUGGAUCUGCUUGCAGUUAUUUGUGUACCUGUUUGUUGGGGUGUGCAUUCUUGUGUAUGUGUGUGUGUGUGUGUGUGUGUGUGUGUGUGUGUGUGAGAGAGAGAGAGAGAGAGAGAAUCUCAGUCUCCCAGAUAGAAUUUUAUAGGCUUAAUGAUGUUUUAAUGUUGCUUGGCAUCCCAUUGCUCUGGCCUCUUCUGGCAUUUACCAAUGACCCUUAACAAACACAUCUACCCAUGUGACCAAAGUCCACUGACACAAGAGGCCAGGAUUCAUACUUGCACAUUAAUGAAAAGUCACAACUGGAAAGCACAGAAAGAGCUGAAAGCAGCCUCCGGUGGCUUCAUUUUGUAGAUGAGUCCGUUUUGUAAUUCUGCAGAAAGGGGGGGAUAUGAACUUCGCACUGCAGUGUCUUCUUGCUCCAUCCUAGGUCUGUCUAUAUCUCUAUCUGGCUAUGAUCCUUUCUAGGGUUGAUGAAUACCCUUUACUGAGUCAACUAUUGCUUUAAAGAAUUUUUUUUGUAGGUUUAUGUACUCAUUUUAGUUAGCAUCUACCUCUCUGGGAAAAUGAAAGGAGGGUUGACUUAGGGAUGAGUAUAGAUGUUGAAAGACAACUAUCAAACCAUGUGGUUUGAAUUUUUAAAAUUGUAAAACAUUGGUGUCCAAACCUCCCACCCCACUUGUAUGUAAAGGACAGUGAGUGUUGUAUAAAUAGUAAACUAUAAGAAGCAUGAAUUUUCAUCUUUAUUAAUGAUCUUGAAAUAAGGAAGAGAAUGCUUAAUAUGUUAAGUAGAGCCAAGAAUGCUACUAAGAAGCAUUGUCUUUGGAAAAAUUUUGUAUAAUGACUUGGGGCAUAAGUUGUGAUGAAAAGGCAACUUGGUUUUUGGUUCCAGUCAUACUUAAUGAUCAGAAAGCUCUAAGAUGUUUUCUUUAAAAAUAGAAUUAAGUUUAAUUUUUUGCAUGGCUUACAGAUUGGGUCCCUUGAAGGUUAAACCAUGUGAUGGUAUAACCUGUGAGAUCUUCUAGAUUGGCACUGUUCAAUAGGGCUUUCUGUGAUGAUGGAAAUGCUCGAAAACCUGUGCCGUCUGGUACGGUAGCCACCAGGCACAUUGACUUUUAGGCAGUUAAAAUGGGGUUACUACAAGGGAAGAACUGGAUUUCAAAUUUUAUUUAAUUUUAAUUAGCUUAAAUUUAAAUAGCCCUAUGUGUCUAGUGGCUGCCAUAUUGAACGAUGCAGUUCUGGGUGAUAGCGCUUGGGGAUCCAGCAUCAAGGUAUUAAUGGAGUAACAGUGAGGCUAAGGUGAGAGUUUGUGGGCUAGUGACAUGCAGUUGGCAAAAGGCAAAACAUUCCUUUCUGGGCUUAAAAAGUAUGUGAUCUCAAGUAUGACAGUAAAAAUUCAUUGUUGCCCUUUGGAACUGUUGCUUAUAGAUUUUAGGCCAAGGAAUGAUCAGUGAAGCUUAAAGAAUGCUUUAUUAAGCCCCUUUUCUGGGAUCAUUAGCUGCAUGUUAACCUAUUGUCCAAAAAUAGUAGUUAGACAGUACCUGUAAAACGUUUGACUUGCAAGCUAUGCAUGAUCUGUACUGUGAAAUUGUGUCUAGGGUCUUGUGGCCAAAAAGUAAAUGUUACAGGAAAAAAAAAGCCUAAUGAAAUCCCUGUUCACUUCCAGUAUCCUAUCCAAACUUCAUUGCUGUAUUAGUAAGGUGCAAAUAUAAGAGCAAGCAUGUUUUGCAGUGUUCAGACUGGUUUUGUUUGCCCUUGAAGUUGGCCAGCUUGUCGUUGUAUUUGGUGUGGGCAUAUGUGGGCAUCAUUUUUCAGAUGCCAAACUAAAAUGUAGGUAGUAUUUUUAGAAUGAGAUUUGACAUUGUUUUAGUGUCUUUCUUUUUUAAGCAAAAAUUUCAGUUAUCCCUGAAAGAGUUGAAGAUUUGAAGCUUUGCACAAAAGCACUUUUUUUAACAGUAAAAAAUACUGCCCAUGAAAUUUAAAGACUUGAAGUUUACUAAAGCUACAAUAAUUACUUUUUAGCUAAAUAAAAGGAAGCAGAAAAUUCAGUUUGAGAUAUAUUUCCUAUAAAGACCAGAUUCUUACUGAUAAUCUGGUAUUUAUUCCAGUCUAGAUUUUGAUUUUAAGAGUUCCCAUCCCUUUAUUUGAAAACUUAUGUUGUUUCAAAAUUGGUUAGUCUGCUUUUCAUUGUUUUCCAAAUGGAAUAUAUACAAAAUACAUUUACUUCAUUUUAGCAGAAAUGGGUUGAUUUUUUUUUUCUAGAACUCAUCAAUGUGCAAGACUUUCCUUCUUAGCUUGCCUUUAAAAAUCAUUUAAUUUUUUUUUUUUUGCCAAGAUACUAAUCUUUCUUUAGCCUUAAUAGGAAGAUAGAAGUUCAAAAGUUAUCGGUGCAAAAGGAGUGAUACACAAAAGACUUCAAUUUCUAUCUUUUCUCAGAAAAGUGAUGCUGCCCACCAGUCAGCAUUUUGUUUCCACAUAAGAAGUGUCAGGUAGUCAGUCUGUCAUCCCUGACUUAGAUAGAGAAGCUGUUCCUUGACAUUUCCAUCAUUCUCAGUAAAUUGUCACCUACAAGGUAAUUCUUACCAAAACAGAAACUAUUGAGAAUAAUAAGAUAGUCGAGAUAAUUCAGUAGCUGUUUUGAAAGUAGUAGUCUAUUUAAAAAGCAACGAUGUUCAGUUGCUGGAUUUUGUUCAACAUGAGACACUUAUUUAUUUAUUUAUUUAUUUAUGAGAUGGAGUUUUGCUCUUGGUGCCCAGGCCAGAGUGCAAUGGCAUGAUCUCAGCUCACUGCAACCUCCGCCUCCCAGGUUCAAGCUAUUCUCCUGCCUCAGCCUCCUGAGUAGCUGGGAUUAUAGGCAUGCGCCUCCAUGCCCAGCUAAUUUUGUAUUUUUUAAAGUAGAGACGGGGUUUCUCCAUGUUGGUCAGGCUGGUCUCCAACUUCUGACUUCAGGCGAUCCACCCGCCUCGGCCUCCCAAAGUGCUGGGAUUACAGGCAUGGGCCACUGCACCCAGCCAACAUGAAACACUUCUAAAAGAUAAGUGGAAAUUCAAGCCAUUGAUUUUUCUGACACAACUGACUUACUACACACACACACACACACACACCACGAUUUAGCUGUAAUUGGAGUUAAAAUUCAGUAAAAAACUGUUAUUAGUCAUGUUUUCCAAUUUGUGAGUUAUACAAUAUUGGAUUAGAUGCUAAUUUCUUAACUGUUGCUAUGGGCUGCAUACAUUAUGUCAAACUAACUACCUUUGGGAGUGUCUAUAUAAACACUUGAAACUUUUCAAAUAUAUGAAGAGGUAGGUUCUACUGUAUACAUUUUAUUGGAAAGCCAUUAAUCAUUGAAGAACUUAAGCAGGUGGGGCAUUUAAUUUCUUCCAAAUACCUUAUUUUUUGGAUCUGCUCAAGUGGUUAGGGCGAGUGCACCAUUAUUCCCGAAUCCCUGCAAUUUGGUUCCCAUUUUUCUGCACAAAUUUUCUUGCUCAGUCGAGCCAAUGACUUUUUUUUUUUUUUUUUUUUUCAGGAUUCACUGCCUGGGGUAUCCCACUAUAUAUAUCUCACCUAUGAUGUAGUGGUGCUUGAAAUACUCAUCUCAUUAGCUCGAUUUUAUUAUUCUAAUCUAAGGUUUUUUAUAUUAUUCAUACUAUGAUAUUUUUAGGGACAAUCAGUAAUAUUUGGGGCAGAGUACUGAGGGACCUCUUGAAGUCUGCAACAGCAUGCAUUUUCUUUGUUUUUGUGGGAGUGCUUCCCUGUAGCUGUCUUUGUUCUAGAACACUGCUCCAAAUUUAUUUCCAUGGGAUGUAGGGCUAGUAGCCCAUGUGAAAGUCUUCUGUAAUCUCCUUGGGGUGUGAGUUAUUGGGUUAUUCUAACAGGAGUUUUCCAAAGGGAUGGCCCAUUUUUAAUUCAACAUUUGCUUUUUGAAAAUCCAGAAGUAGACAGUUGGAUAUAAUAGUGGUGGAAGAGCAUGGGCUGUAAGCAGAAGGAAAUAGAGAUGACAAAUGCCUCUUAAAGGGGAUCUAGUUGAUACCUCUGUUAAAUAGUGGGAGAACACAGUAGCUGGUACCUUACACUGUGCUUUAGGAAAAUCCUAUGAGGAUUUCAUUUACAAAUCCUCAUAGGAUUUUCUGGGUUGAGGGACAAUGCAACUAUUAAGUAGAGGGAGAGGGAGAGGGAAAGGGAGACAUGAAGCACUGGGUCUAUGUGAAGGGACAGGCAGAUAUACCCAAAGAGGGAGAAAAUACUUAAUAAAGGAAGAGUAUAGCUGCAAAACAAGACAUAUAGGAGCUGAAGGCCAGAUAUGGCAGAAACCAGCUGGAGAAAGAAGCACAGGACAACUAGGACAACUUAGUCAAGCACAAUCUGUCAUUCCAGUACGGACUACCAAGUUCAAUUCAGGAUGCUUCAGUUGAAGACAUGUGGGGUAAUGUGCUCAGCUCAUGAGGGUCCAAGGAGUCCCCAUUUUCCCUAUCACCCUAUCCUAUGCUCGUGGUUUGGAUUGUUAGCACACUAGGCAAUUUCAGAGUCCGCUCUAGAGUUGGUUGCCACGUCAGUGCAGACAGACUCUAGAAUCCUCUUAACCAUGGAAUGCAAGGCCUGUUCCUGUGGAUCUAUCCUGACUUGAGUAUGUCAGUACUGUUGGGAAAAUGAGUUCAAGAAUAUUUCAGUUUAUAUAUCCUGGUUGCCGUCAUAUAUUUUUUCAUUUCACCACUUGUUUGUGUUUGCCUCACUCAACAGUCAUGGGUGUAGAAGCUGGUUUCAGCUUGGGGCUGUUACAAACUCCCUACAUAAGCCAUGUAGCUGCAAUCCAGGGUUCCUCCCACCCUACGGCUUUAGCGGUGGGUUCUCUGGCCCUCUUGAUAACAAAUACUCCAGUCUAAUGGCUAUAUUAAUGCUGCUCAGAGGCUAUUAACUCAAAUCCUUGAUGUGUUUCAUUUACAAUUAUGUGGAUUAUUUAUUUUAGGAGCUUUUUUUUUUUUUUUUUUUUUUUUUAAGGGCCAAAUAGCCCUACAGAUAAAUGAGCUGCUGGGCUGUGUAGAAAAUAUUGUCCAAAUGUUGCCAAAUAUUGACUUCGUAAAGGGGAUAUCAAGCUGCUGUUUAUAAAUCUGAAUGUCUUAAAAGCAUUCUUGCUUGCUCUCUCUGUUAUAGAUGGUGUCUUAGCCAGUCCUGAGUUUUCCAAUGAACCCAAUUUUAAUAUAUGGUAUUUUUGUAUGCCAAACUGGUGUCUUGUCCUUUGUAUAUGUGGUAAUGUUGAUUUUAUGACUACCGUAAAAACACAUUUGCUAUGAUUAAAGUUCAUAAAAUGAUUUCAAA